AGAGCUACUGCCAGAGGGAGUCAGUGCAGUCCUGUGUCGGACACGCCCGCAGCCUGGACCCGGGAUCCCCAUCCCCCUAGGAUCUCUGAGCCUCGGGCCUCUGCACCCACAUCCAAGGUGAGUCUCUCGGCUGCCCUGAGCUGGGGCUGGAUGGGCCGGACCCUCCAUUCCGGCUGCAGCUUCCCGCGCAGUGAGAAGGCAGCGGUCCCUGAGAGCCCAGCAGUGCCCUGGGAGCCUGCAGAACGCAGGGGCGGAUUCCGCGUCGCACUGGCCGUCAAGGGGCGGCCGCGGAGGGAAGGGGUGGGUCGGUGGGUCUGACAGCGGGUCUGCGUAGGCGGCAGCGUCUGUCCCUCCCAGCCUCUCGCUCCGCGCCAUGGGCGGGCCCCGGGCUCUGCUGGCCGCACUCUGGGCGCUGGAAGCCGCCGGGACCGCCGCGCUUCGCAUCGGAGCCUUCAACAUUCAGAGCUUCGGUGACAGCAAAGUGUCGGACCCCGCUUGCGGCAGCAUCAUCGCGAAGAUCCUGGCUGGCUAUGACCUCGCGCUGGUGCAGGAGGUGCGAGACCCAGACCUCAGCGCCGUGUCCGCGCUCAUGGAGCAGAUCAACAGCGUGUCCGAGCACGAGUACAGCUUUGUGAGCAGCCAGCCCCUGGGCCGGGACCAGUACAAGGAGAUGUACCUGUUCGUGUACAGGAAAGACGCGGUGUCGGUCGUGGACACCUACCUGUACCCAGACCCCGAGGACGUCUUCAGCCGCGAGCCCUUCGUGGUCAAGUUCUCGGCCCCCGGCACCGGUGAGCGGGCCCCGCCCCUCCCCUCCCGCCGAGCUCUGACGCCCCCACCCCUUCCCGCAGCAGCACAGAACCUGGUGCUGAUCCCGCUGCACGCGGCGCCGCAUCAAGCCGUGGCGGAGAUCGACGCGCUCUACGACGUGUACCUGGACGUGAUCGACAAGUGGGGCACCGACGACAUGCUGUUCCUGGGCGACUUCAACGCCGACUGCAGCUAUGUGCGGGCGCAGGACUGGGCCGCCAUCCGUCUGAGGAGCAGUGAGGUCUUCAAGUGGCUCAUCCCUGACAGCGCCGACACCACGGUGGGCAACUCAGACUGCGCCUACGACCGCAUUGUGGCCUGUGGCGCCCGCCUGCGCCGGAGCCUGAAGCCCCAGUCGGCCACCGUGCACGACUUCCAGGAGGAAUUCGGCCUGGACCAGACUCAGGCUCUUGCCAUCAGCGACCACUUUCCAGUGGAGGUGACCCUCAAGUUCCACCGAUGACUCGAGGCCUGGCUGGGGCAUGCCACCUGCAGACCCUGGCUCUGAGGAAUGGCCCAACAGUGGCCCCUUCAGGGUGGCAGCCACCCUUCAGUGAGGCCCCAAGGCAGAGUCGGCUGGGCGUGGACCAGGGGCCAUGGACACGUGAUGUGCUGCUCUGUACCUCCGUUCCCCAUCUGUGGGACGGGCUGCAUCCAGCGACCUCAUGGGGUGUUGUGAGCCCCAUGAGGGGUGCAGGGGGCACUGCCCGGCAGAUGUCUGCUCAAUAAAUGAGCUGCUCCCGGUCGGGCCCCACA